AGUCCGCGCCUCCUCGCCUCCCUGCGCGCUCCCCGCUGUGCACCGCGCCCCGCGCCCCGCGCCUGCCUCCCCGGCCCGGCCCGGCCCGGCCGGGCGCCGUCCACCCGAGGGAGCCCGCGCCCUGCGACUGCCCGACCCUCCACCCGCCCCACGAGCCGGGCACCGGUGCCAGGUGGUGCCGGGUACUUAUAGGAGCAUCGGCGCAUUCCAUCCUCACAGCAGUCCUGAAAGAAGCCCUGCUGAAUCAAGUGAGAGGAGAGCUGCGGAGCAAUCACCAUGAGUAUCUCAGCUCUUGGAGGCCGCACCAAAGGGAAGCCUCUGCCACCAGGCGAGGAGGAGCGCAAUAACGUUCUCAAGCAGAUGAAAGUGCGAACCACGCUGAAGGGGGACAAGAGCUGGAUUACCAAGCAGGAUGAAUCGGAGGGUCGCACCAUAGAGCUGCCCUCAGGCCGGAGUCGCGCCACAUCCUUUUCAUCAGCUGGGGAGGUUCCGAAGCCUAGGCCUCCGAGCACAAGGGCUCCCACUGGCUACAUCAUCCGGGGAGUGUUCACCAAGCCCAUAGACAGCUCUUCCCAGCCCCAGCAGCAGUUCCCCAAGGCCAACGGGACUCCAAAAAGUGCUGCCAGUCUGGUGAGAACAGCUAACGCUGGUCCUCCCCGCCCCUCCUCCUCUGGCUACAAGAUGACCACUGAGGAUUACAAGAAGCUGGCACCCUACAAUAUCAGGCGCAGCUCUACAUCAGGGGACACCGAGGAGGAGGAGGAGGAGGAGGUGGUGCCAUUCUCCUCAGAUGAACAGAAACGGAGGUCAGAGGCUGCAAGCGGUGUUCUGAGGAGGACAGCUCCCCGGGAGCACUCCUACGUCCUGUCAGCGGCCAAGAAGAGCACUGGCAGUCCUACCCAGGAGACACAGGCACCGUUUAUCGCGAAGAGGGUGGAGGUGGUGGAAGAGGACGGGCCUUCUGAGAAGAGCCAGGACCCACCUGCUCUGGCAAGAUCCACUCCUGGCUCAAACAGUGCGGAUGGAGGCAGGACCAAAGCGUCUCGGGCAAUUUGGAUCGAGUGCCUGCCAAGUAUGCCUAGCCCCGCUGGGAGCCAGGAGCUCAGCUCAAGAGGUGAGGAAAUUGUCCGCCUGCAGAUCCUGACACCCAGGGCAGGACUCCGCCUGGUGGCCCCAGACGUGGAAGGCAUGAGGUCUUCCCCAGGCAACAAAGACAAGGAGGCCCCCUGCUCCAGAGAGCUCCAGAGGGACUUGGCUGGUGAGGAGGCUUUCAGGGCCCCCAACACAGAUGCUGCAAGGUCAAGUGCACAGUUGAGUGAUGGCAAUGUGGGAUCCGGAGCCACGGGCUCCCGGCCUGAAGGCUUGGCUGCAGUAGACAUCGGCUCCGAGAGAGGAAGGCUGUGUGCAGCUGCUAGCUUUGCCUCUUUCCUGGAAGACCAGGAUGGGCACAGUGCCAACUCUCAGUCCUGCAAGCCUAGACCAGCAGCCAUCAGCUCCAGUGCCACUUCAGUCUCUGCUGUCCCUGCUGAUAGGAAGAGCAACAGCACAGCAGCCCAGGAGGAUGCAAAGGCAGACCCAAAGGGGGCCUUGGCUGAUUAUGAGGGGAAGGAUGUGGCCACCAGGGUCGGAGAGGCCUGGCAGGAGAGGCCUGGAGCUCCAAGAGGUGGCCAAGGAGACCCAGCUGUACCCGCUCAGCAACCUGCAGAUCCCAGCACCCCAGAGCGGCAGAGCAGCCCCAGCGGAUCUGAGCAACUUGUCAGACGAGAGAGUUGUGGCAGCAGGAGAGUGCCACAGCCAGACUCGAGUCCAAAGAAGAUCCCUCCAUUGCCCUGUGGAGGACCAGGCCAGGGGAGUAUACGACGAGACAAGGCAGGAGGCCAUAUUGGAGACUGUUUGCUUACACCAGGGGCAAGCGUGUUGACUGAUUUUGAGGGGAAGGAUGUGGCCACCAAGGUCGGAGAGGCCUGGCAGGACAGGCCUGGAGCCCCAAGAGGUGGCCAAGGAGACCCAGCUGUACCCACUCAGCAACCUGCAGAUCCCAGUACCCCAGAACAGCAGAACAGCCCCAGCGGAUCUGAGCAAUUCGUCAGACGAGAGAGCUGCACCAGCAGGGUGAGGAGCCCCUCGAGCUGCAUGGUCACUGUUACUGUCACUGCCACAUCUGAGCAGCCUCACAUUUAUAUUCCAGCCCCCGCAAGUGAAUUGGACUCCAGCUCUACCACCAAAGGGAUUCUCUUCGUGAAGGAGUACGUGAAUGCUAGUGAAGUGUCUUCUGGGAAGCCAGUAUCUGCACGCUAUAGCAACGUCAGCAGCAUUGAGGACUCAUUCGCCAUGGAGAAGAAGCCUCCAUGUGGCAGCACUCCAUACUCUGAGAGGACAACUGGAGGGAUCUGUACUUACUGCAACCGUGAGAUCCGAGACUGUCCAAAGAUUACCCUAGAACAUCUUGGUAUCUGCUGCCAUGAAUAUUGCUUUAAGUGUGGGAUUUGCAGUAAACCGAUGGGCGAUCUCCUGGAUCAGAUCUUCAUUCACCGUGACACCAUUCACUGUGGGAAAUGCUAUGAGAAGCUCUUCUAGCGACCCCCCACCGCCAGGCUGAUCAGAAGCUGAUGACUCGUGGACAAAUUUGGCUGUCCCCAGUUUUGCCCCAAGUUGCUGUCUCCCCUUCCCUCACCUCCUCCCUCCCUGUUUGAUUUCUUCAUGCUUUUGCCCUUCUCAAGUUGAAGUUGCAUACAUCCAAUAUCGUAUCUUAAUGAUGCUAUGAUAAUUGCUUGUGUGUGUAGCUUCUUGUAGCUUAGAAAGCGCUUUAUGCCCAUGAUGUCAUUUCAGGCUCAACCAAAGAGGAUCAAACAGGAAUUCCAUCUUGGCUUCCCUAAGACAGAUUGGCUUUCUAAUGAGUUUAAGUGGGCAGAAGUGUAGGGUUCAGUGUGUCCUGACUCCCUUGAGGCUUAUAAUGGGCCAAGUUGAAGACUGUUGAUGAUCCCUGGUGGGUAAAUUGCAGACAUCAAAUGCUAGGGAUUGGCAUAGGCUAGUGUUUAGCUUGUCUAUUUGCCAUAUCUAUUUUUUUUAAAUUUCCAUACACUUGUAAAAGUAGUUAGUUGCUUUUGAUUGAGUUAUAUAGCAGUUUUUCAUUUGGUCUUCCACUCACCUUUCACUAUAUUUGAGUGUUCCCUUACAGGUAUGUUGGCAUGUGUUGGAAAAUUUACACAAUUAGGUUUAAAUUCAGUAGGAUGUGAUUUUAGGAUGCUACUGAUCAAAGUGAUAUCUGUGUCUGUUGGAAUCUUGAUAGCUGAUUAAUUUGCCCUCAAUUCUGCUCCCUGAACUUCACACAUAAAUCUUCCCAAGUGGGUUUUAGGGUGUAUAGAUCCCAGCAGGAUUAAGGAGGUGGAAAAGCAGCUAACAUUUCUUGAGGCUCUACCACAUAGCAGGCACUGUCACAGAGUAAUGGCAUUAAUCCCCAUAAUAAUCCUGUGAAGGUGAUAUUCUCAUCCCAUCUUAGACAUGAGGAUAUUGGAACUCAGAGAGGUGGCUAUUGCAUUGCGCAGAACGCUACAGAGCCCAUGCUCUUCCCAGAGCAGCACCCACAAAAGCAAGCAUUGAUUUUGUGCUCAGUGUGUGCCAAGCACUGUGCAGAGGGUACACAGUUCCUGCCAGGUUAACACCCUCCCUUCAGGCCUCCCAAAGGCAUAGGCUUGCAAAGAGCAGAAGGUGUGAAAUCACACUCUUCCUCUGGGCAUCCUGGAUCCCUGAAUUAUCCCCCCCCCCAUGAAGUACUUCAAGGGCCAAGCUGCCCCUUUCCCUCCUCUCCGCCCAUGAAAAUGCCUCCAAACUGAGAUGCUUUCAGCUGAGAACAGAUUUGACUCACAGACAUUACCAAAGAGGAGCUUGUGAAUCCAGGAAAAGCUCCAGGGGGCUAGCUGAUCUGAGCAGAGAGCUUUCAGUGACCCAUUUUCCUGUCUAGACUCUGCCUUAAGCUAGUGGCAACUGCUGGGGCCCCAGGUACUUGGGACAUGGAAACUCGUUGGAUGGCUGGGCAGAUGUAAGCCUGUCCAUGCAGUCAGCCGAUCCUCUGCUCAGGUUCAGCUGGACUCUGCCAUCUGUGGGCCCAGCAUCACUCUGUAAGUUCCUUGAAAGGAAGAACAACCUUAGAGUAUUUCUGAUACAAAAUGAGGGCCUCUGCUCUUGAUUUAAUUAUAAAAUGUCUACGUCUUUCUCCAGUUUCUGAGCCCUAUGCACAUUGGCUUGUGGGCUUGUUCUUCCUGCCAAAUGAUCAGAGAGGAACAUUCCAUUUAUUUGUAGUGGAUUUCCUCUGGAGGGCAUGUACCCACACUAAAUACCAACUGCUCUUCCUCAGCUGUAGUCCCCAACAUCAGACUUGGCACGUGGUGGACACUAACACACAGGCACUCAAUGAAUGAGUGAAGGAAAUAAAAGUCACCCCGUUGGUGAGAGGUGCUAUCCCUGAGUCUCAGUGCAGGACCAGUGGAUGAAAGGCAAGGUAAAGAGGCCCAAGAUAGGCUGGCUUCCCCCGUUCAAGGUAUAGUCUGCCUUUAAGGGAGUUUUAGAACCAACAUGCAAGACAUUGAAAGAAAUCUUGCAAGAGCCAUUAUUGACUUAGAUCCAAAACAGCCUCUCUCAUGUCUAAAAAGGCACAGAAUUUUGCAGAUCUGAGGAAGAGGGAUGCAUUACCUUUUUGCUUCUUUUCAAUUGCUUAGUGUUUCUAAUCAUACUUAAUCCACACUAAUGUGCGCAAUUAUAAUAAAUGGUAAGAUAUCACAUGUGUCA